CUCCAUGCGGCGCCCUCACCAGCCUACAGGCGGCACCGCAGCAGCCUCCAGGCAGCGCCCACACCAGCCUACAGGGGUCGCCGCUCGCACUGCACCUGCCUCCGCCGCCCCGGGGUGUGAACUGCGCUGUCUGUCGGCCUGGCUACGCUGACCCGGGCAGCCCAGGCCCGCAGCAGCCGGACGAGGAGCCCAGGGCCACUGCCCGGGGUUACGAGAAGGAGCAGGACGGUGCCCCAGAAAAAUGCAAGAGCUCAGAGCUAGGGCCCCCGUGCCAGGAAAGGCUAGGAGCAGAAGAUGGAGAGAUGGAGAUGGAGAAGCGGCAGGUGGGAAGGAGCGGCGCUCCACCGGUGGGGUCAGCAUGCGCUGGCGGGGCUUAGAGUAUGAAGAGGAAGAAGCUGGGCAGAAAGAGCGGAAACGAGAAGGUGCAAUGACACAACAGAGCACAAUGCAGAAUCCAGCCCUAGGACUCCAAUAAAGGCUGGGUUUAAUUGCAACUCACACACCCCACCCCUAAUCAGAGAGGAUCAGGGGAGAGAGAGGACCCAAGGAACACUGGAACCUGAAGGGCGGGAAUCUGAGGCCAAGACUGAUUGUUGGAAAUUGUGGGCAUCAGGAAAGGAGAAAAACCAAAGAUUGGAUCUUCUGAGAACAUCAGAGAAAGAAUGUCCUUGCCAUCCACAAUACAGCAAAACUUCAGGACCUUGAACUUUGGGUUCAUAAUCUCACAAGAGGGAAGUUUUUCGCCAGAAAAAGAUGGCAUCCUUGAUGUGAACAGCUUUUCCCAAGAUCACAGAUCAAGACUUCUAGUUUUUUUUUUUGAGACAGAGUCAUUUUUUUUUUUUUUUUUGAGACAUAGUCUCGGUCUUGUUGCUCAGGUUGGAGUGGAAUAGCGCGAUCUUGGCUCACUGCAACCUCCGCCUCCUGGGUUCAAGUAAUUCUCCUGACUCAGCCUCCAGAGUAGCUGGGAUUACAGGCGCCCACCACCAUGCCCGGCUAAUUUUUUUGUAUUUUUAGUGGAGACAGGGUUUCACCAUGUUGGCCAGGCUGGUCUCGAACUCCUGACCUCAGGUGAUCCGCCUACCUCGGCCUCCCAAAGCGCUGGGAUUACAGGCAUCAGUCACCGUGCCCGGCCUUGUGAUAGUGUCUUACUCUGGCACCCAGGCUGGAGUGCAGUGGUGCAAUCUUGGUUCACUGCAACCUUCGCCUCCCAGAUUCAAGCGAUUCUUGUACAUCAGCCUCCCGAGCCGCUGAGACUACAGGCACGUGCCACCAUGCCUGGUUAAUUUUGUGUGUGUGUGUGUGUGUAUGUUUGUGUGUGAUGGAGUUUUGCUCUUGUUGCCCAGGCUGGAGUGCAGUGGUGCGAUCUUCGCUCACUGCAACGUCUGCCUCCCGGGUUCAAGCGAUUCUCCUGCCUCGGGCUCCUGAGUAGUUGGGAUUAUAGGCGCUCAACACCAUACCCGGGGAAUUUUUUGUAUUUUUAGUAGAGACGGGGUUUCAUCAUGUUGGCCAGGUUGGUCUCCAACUCCUGACCUCAGGUGAUCCACCCGCCUCGGUGUCCCAAAGUGCUGGGAUUACAGGCGUGAGCCCUGUGCCCAGCCUCAGUGUCUCUCUCUCUCUCGACUAGAGAGACUGACCAGGGACAAUCAACUCUCUCCAGACUGACAGAGAGAGAGACAGAGAGAGCGAGAAAGAGACAGAGUCUGGCUCUCACCCAGGCUGGAGUGCAGUGGUGUGAUCUUGGCUCACUGCAACCUCUGCCUUCCGUGUUCAAGCGAUUCCUGUGCCUCAGCCUCCCAAGUAGCUGGGAUUAUAGGUCCACACCACCACGCCCGGCUAAUUUUUGUGUUUUUAGUAGAGACAGCCUCACCAUGUUGGCCAGGCUGGUUUUGAACUCCUGACCUCAGGUGAUCCGCCAGCCUCGGCCUUCCAAAGUGCUGGGAUUACAGGCGUGAGUCACCGCGCCCGGCCAAAUAAAAUAAAAUGUUAAAGCAAAUUCAGGACUACCCCUCCUCCAAGUCUUCUGUUCCCUUUGGGCGCCCAGGUGAGCGGGGGAGGGGCUGGGGGAGUAAUAACAUCAAAAGAGCGCCUUUUCCUCCCUUAUUCCGAGGAGACUUCCCUGGGCCUGACUCCCGGUCCUGUCCCCAGCGCCCCGCGGCCUCUGGAGCCCCUUCAGUGACCAAGAUACAGAGAUCAGGACGCCUUUGCGCCGCCCCAGGUGCCCGCCCCUAGCUGGCUCUGCUUGGGCCGCGAGGGAAGGUGAGGUCGGGGGCGGAGCCGGGGCGUGACAGCCGGGGUGUGUGUCCGCCGGGCUUGGUGCCUCCGGUGGCCCUGCAGCACCGUCCCACCUCUGCCACCCUCCGAUGGGGCCGCUACCUGUGUGCCUGCCAAUCAUGCUGCUCCUGCUACUGCCGUCGCUGCUGCUGCUGCUGCUUCUACCUGGCCCCGGGUCCGGCGAGGCCUCCAGGAUAUUACGUGUGCACCGGCGUGGGAUCCUGGAACUGGCAGGAACUGUGGGUUGUGUUGGUCCCCGAACCCCCAUCGCCUAUAUGAAAUAUGGUUGCUUUUGUGGCUUGGGAGGCCAUGGCCAGCCCCGCGAUGCCAUUGACUGGUGCUGCCAUGGCCACGACUGUUGUUACACUCGAGCUGAGGAGGCCGGCUGCAGCCCCAAGACAGAGCGCUACUCCUGGCAGUGCGUCAAUCAGAGCGUCCUGUGCGAGUCUCGCUCUGUCGCCCAGUCUGGAGUGCAAUGGCGUGAUCUCGGCCCACUAAAACCUCCACCUCCUGAAUCUCAGCAAUUCUCCUGUCUCAGCCUCCUGAGUAGCUGGGACUACAGGCUGACACCACCAUGCCCGGCUAAUUUUUGUAUUUUUAAUAGGGACGAGGUUUUGCCAUAUUGGUCAGGCUGGUCUCGAAGUCCUGGCCUCUGGUGAUCCACCAGCCUCAGCCUCCCAAAAUGCUGGGAUUACAGGCAUGAGUCACCAUGCCCAGCCUAAACUUGGCAAGAUAAUAAAUAACCUUUUAAAGUGUCGUUGGGCACUUGUCUGGUUGUUUUUCUUUAGGUUACCAUGCCAGCAAUGAUUCCUUUUGAGUUUCUGACAGAAGAUAGUGGUUUUCAUCCAAAUAAGUCAACUACUCUACCCCAUCCCUAAGCCACUUGUAUGGAAAGAAAAAGAGGAAGAAGCCAGUACUGAGACUGCGUAAGCUUCCCCCAGCAUCACCCGCUAUGAGAUGUGUGGCAGCUGAGACCCGGGAACUGCUCAAGGGCACCAGGCCCCAUCUGUCUGCACUCACUCACCUUCCU